GAGAACGAAAGAUGGCGGCGCCCGUAAGGCGGACGCUGUUAGGGGUGGCGGGGGGUUGGCGGCGGUUCGAGAGGCUCUGGGCCGGCAGUCUAAGCUCUCGCAGCCUGGCUCUUGCAGCCGCACCCUCAAGCAACGGAUCCCCAUGGCGCUUGUUGGGCGCGUUGUGCCUGCAGCGGCCACCUGUAGUCUCCAAGCCGUUGACCCCAUUGCAGGAAGAGAUGGCGUCUCUACUGCAGCAGAUUGAGAUAGAGAGAAGCCUGUAUUCAGACCACGAGCUUCGUGCUCUGGAUGAAAACCAGCGACUGGCAAAGAAGAAAGCUGACCUUCAUGAUGAAGAAGAUGAACAGGAUAUAUUGCUGGCGCAAGAUUUGGAAGAUAUGUGGGAGCAGAAAUUUCUACAGUUCAAACUUGGAGCUCGCAUAACAGAAGCUGAUGAAAAGAAUGACCGAACAUCCCUGAACAGGAAGCUAGACAGGAACCUUGUCCUGUUAGUCAGAGAGAAGUUUGGAGACCAGGAUGUUUGGAUACUGCCCCAGGCAGAGUGGCAGCCUGGGGAGACCCUUCGAGGAACAGCUGAACGAACCCUGGCCACACUCUCAGAAAACAACAUGGAAGCCAAGUUCCUAGGAAAUGCACCCUGUGGGCACUACACAUUCAAGUUCCCCCAGGCAAUGCGGACAGAGAGUAACCUCGGAGCCAAGGUGUUCUUCUUCAAAGCACUGCUAUUAACUGGAGACUUUUCCCAGGCUGGGAAUAAGGGCCAUCAUGUGUGGGUCACUAAGGAUGAGCUGGGUGACUAUUUGAAACCAAAAUACCUGGCCCAAGUUAGGAGGUUUGUUUCAGACCUCUGAUGGGCCGAGCUGCCUGUGGACGGUGCUCAGACAAGUCUGGGAUUAGAGCCUCAAGGACAUUGUGUGAUUGCCUCACAUUUGCAGGUAAUAUCAAGCAGCAAACUAAAUUCUGAGAAAUAAACGAGUCUAUUACUG